AUCUCCCAUCUCUUUUCCCCUGUUACCACCUGCUCAUUCACCCCUACCUCCUUCAUUUGUCAUUACUGGGUUAAUAUCCUUUAAAAACUAACAGGACCUCCGCUUCUGGGAAGAUGGAGUAGAUGUACUUUUCUCUAUUCUUUCUGUCAAGUACAACUAAAAACCCUGGAUAUUACAUAAAUUAUAAAUAAUUUAGUAAGUAUGUAAUAUAUAAAAAGCCUCUUAAAAGGCAGAGAGAAGAAGGCAGACCAGCUAAGGACCUCAGGACCCAAGAAAUGGUGCAGUGAUGAGUUCUCUAGGUUUUCUUUUUGUUUCUUAUGUCCCAGACUUGGAGUUGAAGCAGCCGGCAACCCAGAAAUACCAGUAAGCUCAGACGCAAAAAGCCCCAACAAAAAUUUGCUCUCUCUAGCCAAAUGACCAGUGCAGUAGGACAGAACAAGUGGGUUUGUUCCAGGGAUAUAAGGAUGGUUCAUUAUUUGAAAAUUAAUCUCAUCCACCAAAUUAAUGAACUAAAAGAAGAAAACUUACAUGAUGCUCUCUAUCAAUGCAGAAGAUGCAAAAUUUAGCACACAUUUAUGAUUUUAAAAAUCUCAGGAAAAAUAGACAUAGAGGGGGAUUUUCCUGAACUUGAUAAAGGGUAAACACCAUAAGCCUUCAGCUAACAUACUUAAGGGUGAGACUGAAUGCUUUGUCCCUAAGAUGGGGAACAAACCAAGGAUAUUAGUUCUCACCGCUUAUCCAACAUAGUGCUGUAAUUUCUAGCCAGUGCAAUAAGGUAAGAAAUGGAAGUAAAAGUCAUAUAGAUUGGAAAAGAAGGAAUAAGACCCCAUAUUUGCAGAUUACAUGAUUGUGUACAUAGAAGAUCCCAAGGCAUCCACAAAAAAACUCCUAGAACUAAUAAGUAAGUUUAGCAGGGUUACAAGAUACAAGAUAACACACAAAAAUCAAUUGCAUUUCUGUAUACUAGCAAUGAACAUAUGGAUAUCAAAUUUUAAAACAAUACAGUUUCGACCGGAUGUGGUAGUUCAUGCCUGUAAUCCCAGCACUUUGGGAGGAUGAGGUGGGAGGAUCACUUGAGUCCAGGAGUUCAAGAUCAGCCUGGGCAACAUGGUGAGACCCUGUCUCUGCAAAAAAUACAAAAAUUAGCUGAACCUGGUGGUGCAUGCCUGUAGUCCCAGCUACUGGGGAGGCUGAGGUGGAAAGAUUGCUUGAGUGUGGCAGGCGGAGGCUGCAGUGAGCCGAGAUCAUGCUACCGCACUCCAGCCUAGGCAACAGAGUGAGACCCUGUCUCAAAAAAUAAAAUAAAAUGAAAUAAAAUAAAACAAAACAAAACAAUACCAUUUGUAGUUGCUCAAAAAAAGAGAGAAAUAGAUGUAACAAACAUGUUACACAUAACACAGCAUGUGUAGGAUUUGUUUUUUGUUUUGUUUUUGUUUGUUUGGUUGGGUUUUUUUGAGACGGAGUUUCACUCUUGUUGCCCAGGCUGCAGUGCAAUGGUGCGAUCUCGGCUCACUUUGACCUCCGCCUCCUGGGUUCAAGUGAUUCUUCUGCCUCAGCCUCCCGAGGAGCUGGGAUUACAGGCACCCCCUCACCAUGCCCGGCUGGUUUUUUGUAUUUUUAGUAGAGUCAGGGUUUCACCAUGUCGGCCAGGCUGGUCUUGAACUCCUGACCUCAGUUGAUCCACCUGCCUCGGCCUCCCAAAGUGCUGGGGUUACAGGGAUGACCCACCAUGCCCGGCCGCAUGUAUGGUUUAAAUGCUGAAAACGACACAACACUGAUGAAAGAAAUCAAAGAUCUAUGUAAAUGGAAACCCCAUACUGUACUCAGGAAUUGGAAGACUCAACAAAGUAAAGAUGCCAACUUUCCCCAAAUUGAUAUACAGGUUUAGCACACUUUCUAUAAAAAUCCCAGUCAUAUUUUUUAUAGAUGAAGACAAGAUUACUCUAAAAUUUAUAUGGAAAGGCAAAGGAAAUAGAAUAGCUAAAAGAAUUUUGAAGAAGAAAAAUAAAGUAGCAGCACAUAUAUCAAUGAAUCAAAAUAGAAAAUCCAGAAAUAGGCCCACCCAAAUAUGCCCAACCAAUUUUUGACAAAAGUGCAAAAGCAAUUCAAUAGAGGAAAGAUAACGUUUUCAAAAAAUGGCGCUGGAGCAAAUGGACACAAAACUUAGACCUAAGUCUGACGUCUUAUACAAAAAUUAAUGGAUCAUAGACUUAAGAAGUAAAACAUAAAACUAUAAAACUUUUUUUUUUUUUGAGACAGGGUCUCCCUCAGUCCCCCAGGCUGGAGUGCAGUGGUGCAAUCUCAGCUCAUUGCAACCUCUGCCUCCUGGGCUCAGUUGAUCUUCCUGCCUCAGCCUUCCAAGUAGCUGGGACUUAAAGGCGUGAGCCACCACACCUGACUAAUUUUCGUAUUUUUUGUAGAGAUGGGGUUUCGCCAUGUUGCCCGGGCUGUUCUCGAACUCCUGAGCUCAAGCAAUCUGCCCACCUCAGCCUCCCAAAGCGCUGGGAUUACAGGCAUGAGCCACCAUCCCAGCCAAAACUAUAAAACUUUUAGAAAAGAACAUAGAAGAAAAUCUUUGGGUCCUGGGGGCAAAGAGCUCUGAGACUUGACAUCAAAAGCAUGCCGCAUAAUAGGAAAAUACUAGACUUUAUUUAGGGGUUAAGAGUUUAGACUCUGGACUCUCUCAGCCUUGGUUUCACUAGUUAGCUCUAUCACUAACUACAUUGGGCAUUGAAAAUUCCUCUGUUGUCCCACGUGGUGCAUGGAUGAUUGUAGACGAGGACACUGAGAUCCUGAAGGCAGAAGUAAUUUCUCUAAGCAACGUUGUUGGUUGGUGGCAGAGUCUGGGUUACAACCCCUGGUUUCCUGAUUCCGAGUCCAAGUGAAAUACUUUUGCCCCUGCAGUAGACCCUGCUACAGAGGAUAAAAAGGCACGUCAUAGGCUAGGAGAAAAAUUUUGCCUACCACAUAUGUAACCAAGGACUAGCAGCUAGGACAUCUGAAGAAUUCUCAACAUUCAACGGGGUAGAAGAAUGAACGAUUCAAUAGAAUAUGGGCAAAAGACAUGAAGAGGCAUUUUACCAAACAUAGGGUGCUAUGGUCCGAAUGUUUGCAUUCUCCUCAAAUUCCUGUGUUGAAAUCCUAACCCCCAAGGUAUUGGUAUUAGGAGGCAGGGGCCCUGGGAAGUGAUUAGGUCAUAAAGGUGGAGUCCUCAUGGAUGGGAUUAGUGUCUUUAUAAAAGAGACCUUUGCCAUGUGAGGUUACAGUGAGAAGACAUCUGUCUAUGAAGAAAGUGGGCCCUCACCAAACACAGUCUGCUGGCACUUUGCACUUCAACUCCCCAGCUUCCAGAACUGUAAGGAAUAUAAGUCUGUUGUUGGUAAGCCACCCGGUCUAUGAUAUUUUGUUAUAGCAGCCCAAACAGACUAAGACAGGUGACAAAUAAACAUGAAAAGAUGUUCAACAUCAUUAGCCAUUAGGGAAAUGCAGAUUAAAACCACAGCGAAAUAUCAUGAUACAGUUUUCAGCAUGGCUAAACUAGAAAAUAGUGACACCACCAAAUGCCGACAAGGCUGUGGGGAAACUGGGUUGUUCAGACACUGCCACUGGGGCUGUAGCGUACUAUAGCCACUUUCAUAAACAGUUUGUCAGUUUCUUAAAAAACUAAACCUGCAACUACCAUAUGACCCAGCAAUUACACCCCUGGGCACCUACCCAAGAGAAAUGAAAACUCAACGUUUGCGCAAAAACCUGUGUAGGAAUGUUCAAGCAGCUUUAUUCAUAAUAUGCCCAAACAGGAAACAACUCAGCUGUCCUUCAGUAGGUAAAUAGUUAAGCAAAUUGUCAUACCCCUGUGUCAUGGAGCACUACCUAGCAAUAACAAGGAGCAAAUUAUUGAUACAUAACAAUCUGGAUGAAUCUCCAGAGAAUUAUGUUGAAUGAAAAAAGCCAGCCCCUGAAGGAUACAUACUGUAUGAUGCCAUUUACAUAACAUUCUUGAAAUUCUAAAAUUACAGAGAUGGGGAACAGAUUUGUGGUUAAAGAUGGAGCCGGGUGGGAAGAAAGUAGGUGUGGCUAUAAACGGGUAACAUGAAGGAUCCUUGUGGUGAUGGAAAUUUCUGUAUUUUUAUUGUAUCCGUGUCAGUAUCCUGGUUGUGAUAUGGUAAUACAGUUUUGCAAGAUACUACCCUUAGGGGAAAUGAGACGCCCACUAUUGCUUGGUUCUACUUCCUUUAUCCCGAUUGGCCGUCGGACUUAUGCCAGUGCGGCGGAGCCGGUUGGCAGCAAAGCUGUCCUGGUCACAGGCUGUGACUCUGGAUUUGGGUUCUCAUUGGCCAAGCAUCUGCAUUCAAAAGGCUUCCUUGUGUUUGCUGGCUGCUUGAUGAAGGACAAAGGCCAUGAUGGGGUCAAGGAGCUGGACAGCCUAAACAGUGACCGAUUGAGAACCGUCCAGCUCAAUGUCUGCAGCAGCGAAGAGGUGGAGAAAGUGGUGGAGAUUGUCCGCUCGAGCCUGAAGGACCCUGAGAAAGGCAUGUGGGGCCUCGUUAACAAUGCCGGCAUCUCAACGUUCGGGGAGGUGGAGUUCACCAGCCUGGAGACCUACAAGCAGGUGGCAGAAGUGAACCUUUGGGGCACAGUGCGGAUGACGAAAUCCUUUCUCCCCCUCAUCCGAAGGGCCAAAGGCCGCGUCGUCAAUAUCAGCAGCAUGCUGGGCCGCAUGGCCAACCCGGCCCGCUCCCCGUACUGCAUCACCAAGUUCGGGGUAGAGGCUUUCUCGGACUGCCUGCGCUAUGAGAUGUACCCCCUGGGCGUGAAGGUCAGCGUGGUGGAGCCCGGCAACUUCAUCGCUGCCACCAGCCUUUACAGCCCUGAGAGCAUUCAGGCCAUCGCCAAGAAGAUGUGGGAGGAGCUGCCUGAGGUCGUGCGCAAGGACUACGGCAAGAAGUACUUUGAUGAAAAGAUCGCCAAGAUGGAGACCUACUGCAGCAGUGGCUCCACAGACACGUCCCCUGUCAUCGAUGCUGUCACACACGCCCUGACCGCCACCACCCCCUACACCCGCUACCACCCCAUGGACUACUACUGGUGGCUGCGAAUGCAGAUCAUGACCCACUUGCCUGGAGCCAUCUCCGACAUGAUCUACAUCCGCUGAAGAGUCUCGCUGUGGCCUCUGUCAGGGAUCCCUGGUGGAAGGGGAGGGGAGGGAGGAACCCAUAUAGUCAACUCUUGAUUAUCCACGUGUGGAUUAUCCACCAUGCCAGGAAGACCCAUAACUGGUUUUAACACUAACUAGAGGGAAUGACUUCUUUGCAUAGUGAGUGACUUGGGCCUUCACAAACAGGGUGUGGAGUGGCAGGCAGAGGCCUCUAAAUCUCAGGGCAAACAUGGUGAAUCUAUCUCUCCGGAGAUAAUUUCAUACAGAGAUUUUAAGAAAACAUCUUUAUAUUAAAAACAGAUCUCAUUUGAUCCUUAAGCCAGUCUCAUGAAUGAAAAGGACAGGUUUUUUUCUUUUGUAAAUGAAGCAUUUGCAGCUUAAAGAGGAUGCAUGAAAUAACCCUUUUAUCGCUUAUAAAUAGUGCCAGUUAUGUGUUCCUGCCACGGCUGUGGAAAUACUUCACAUUUGCAUUCCAGGACUGUUUUGGAUCCAUUUGCCCGAGAAUCUUCUGACUAACUCUGUGUCCUCAUCUGGGCAGCACACACCAAGUGCCCACUGGUACCUCUGCAUGUCCAUGGUGCUGUGUGACUGGCCAGCCAGCAGCCAGUGACUCAGAGCUGGCUGUAUGGAGGGGGUGGGAAUGUUUCUGGAGAUUUUUGUUUUUCCAGACACAGUCUUGCUCAGUCCCCUAGGCUGGAGUGCAAUGGCACCAUCUCCGCUCACUGCAACCUCCGCCUCCCUGGUUCAAGCGGUUCUCCUGCCUCAGCCUUCCAAGUAGCUGGGGUUAUAGGCACCCACCACCAUGCCGGGCUAAUUUUUGUAUUUUUAGUAGAGAUGGGGUUUCACCAUGUUGGCUAGGCUGGUCCCGAACUCCCGACUUCAAGUGAUCCGCCUGCCUUGGCCUCCCAAAGUGCUGGGAUUACAGGCAUGAGAUUUUUACUUGAGAUUUUUCCAUCCUCUUUUAGGACUCAGGAUAGACUUGUGUGGAGGUGCUCUCUGGCUAAGGGGAUAAGUUGUUACUGGUUUGGGUCUGCUUGGUUUUGCCUUGGGUGGGGCCGGUGUCGAUGGGGCAGGCUUGGCACGAGCAGUGGUGCCAUGGCAGGGCACUGUGGCAUCUCCCCUAGCAGUGGAUUUGGGGUCCCUGCUUGCCUCACGUGGUGCUUACACACAUGUACACACACACACACACACACACACACACACACACCUUACACACAUGUACACACACACACACACACACACACACACACACACACACACACACACACACACACACACACACACACACACACCCCUGUUCUGCAGGGCUUCAGCGUGGCCUUCAUUCCCGCCUCGCCUCGGCCUCUUUUCAAUUAAGAAGUGAUGCCACUUGAGGCAGGGUCUGCAUGAUCACUUCUUGGGUUUCAGUUUGAAAGCUGCCAUCCCUGCGACUGCCCAGGGCCUGUAUGUUGGGACCGAAGCCAAACACCACUGUCCUCCAGGGGGCUUUCGGCCCGGGGCAGGGUCCCCAGUGCCCGCCUUCGAAUCAGACUCCGCGUUUCCGCCUCUCCCUGGGCGGACCUGCCGCUAGAGGGCGCUCCUCCUCCGCAGCCGGCGCCGGCCUCCAGCGCCCCAGACUCCCGCGCUGCCGCCCGAGCCUGAGGUUUCUCACGGCGUUCGGGAUUCGCGCUUCGGAAACCGGGAACAAAGAAGCAAGCAGCACCCUUCAGAAACAGUGUUCUCGCUCUCCUAGCAGCUGGCCCGGGCCCGGAGGCUGGUGCCAGGAGAAGGCAGAAGAGCCCGGGCAGCCGGAGUGGGCUACGGGGUUCAGGCAGUGCCAAGGAAGAAGGGCCUCACAAUGGGCAAUUCAGCUGCCUCCCGGGCCGUUGUCCCCGCUGUCUUCAAACAGGGGUCCCCUGUCCCAGCUGCCCCAGGAGGAGGGGGGGAGGCAGGCAGGGCCGAAACCCUCCAGAGCCCAGAGGGGGACGCUUGGUGGCCGCUGCAGUUACAUAACCAUAGGAUGCUUUUGUACCGUGGACCUUGUUCUAGCAGGAUCCUUUCGGAAUUGCACUUUUACAUGUUGGGCGAAUUUGUGUCCGUGCUGAAGUUUAUUAAAGGAAAAUAGAUGGA